GCUCAUUUGUAGGCUGAACUAAUGACUGCCGCCAUAAGAAGACAGAGAGAACUGAGUAUCCUCCCAAAGGUGACACUGGAAGCAAUGAACACCACAGUGAUGCAAGGCUUCAACAGAUCUGAGCGGUGCCCCAGAGACACUCGGAUAGUACAGCUGGUAUUCCCAGCCCUCUACACAGUGGUUUUCUUGACCGGCAUCCUGCUGAAUACUUUGGCUCUGUGGGUGUUUGUUCACAUCCCCAGCUCCUCCACCUUCAUCAUCUACCUCAAAAACACUUUGGUGGCCGACUUGAUAAUGACACUCAUGCUUCCUUUCAAAAUCCUCUCUGACUCACACCUGGCACCCUGGCAGCUCAGAGCUUUUGUGUGUCGUUUUUCUUCGGUGAUAUUUUAUGAGACCAUGUAUGUGGGCAUCGUGCUGUUAGGGCUCAUAGCCUUUGACAGAUUCCUCAAGAUCAUCAGACCUUUGAGAAAUAUUUUUCUAAAAAAACCUGUUUUUGCAAAAACGGUCUCAAUCUUCAUCUGGUUCUUUUUGUUCUUCAUCUCCCUGCCAAAUACGAUCUUGAGCAACAAGGAAGCAACACCAUCGUCUGUGAAAAAGUGUGCUUCCUUAAAGGGGCCUCUGGGGCUGAAAUGGCAUCAAAUGGUAAAUAACAUAUGCCAGUUUAUUUUCUGGACUGUUUUUAUCCUAAUGCUUGUGUUUUAUGUGGUUAUUGCAAAAAAAGUAUAUGAUUCUUAUAGAAAGUCCAAAAGUAAGGACAGAAAAAACAACAAAAAGCUGGAAGGCAAAGUAUUUGUUGUCGUGGCUGUCUUCUUUGUGUGUUUUGCUCCAUUUCAUUUUGCCAGAGUUCCAUAUACUCACAGUCAAACCAACAAUAAGACUGACUGUAGACUGCAAAAUCAACUGUUUAUUGCUAAAGAAACAACUCUCUUUUUGGCAGCAACUAACAUUUGUAUGGAUCCCUUAAUAUACAUAUUCUUAUGUAAAAAAUUCACAGAAAAGCUACCAUGUAUGCAAGGGAGAAAGACCACAGCAUCAAGCCAAGAAAAUCAUAGCAGUCAGACAGACAACAUAACCUUAGGCUGACAACUGUACAUAGGGUUAACUUCUAUUUAUUGAUGAGACUUCCGUAGAUAAUGUGGAAAUCAAAUUUAACCAAGAAAAAAAGAUUGGAACAAAUGCUCUCUUACAUUUUAUUAUCCUCGUGUACAGAAAAGAUUAUAUAAAAUUUAAAUCCACAUAGAUCUAUUCAUAAGCUGAAUGAACCAUUACUAAGAGAAUGCAACAGGAUACAAAUGGCCACUAGAGGUCAUUAUUUCUUUCUUUCUUUUUUUUUUUUUUUAAUUUCAAGAGCAUUUCACUUUAACAUUUUGGAAAAGACUAAGGAGAAACGUAUAUCCCUACAAACCUCCCCUCCAAACACCUUCUCACAUUCUUUUCCACAAUUCACAUAACACUACUGCUUUUGUGCCCCUUAAAUGUAGAUAUGUGCUGAAAGAAAAAAAAAACGCCCAACUCUUGAAGUCCAUUGCUGAAAACUGCAGCCAGGGGUUGAAAGGGAUGCAGACUUGAAGAGUCUGAGGAACUGAAGUGGGUCAGCAAGACCUCUGAAAUCCUGGGUAAAGGAUUUUCUCCUUACAAUUACAAACAGCCUCUUUCACAUUACAAUAAUAUACCAUAGGAGGCACAAGCACCAUUAUUAAGCCACUUUGCUUACACCUUAAGUGUGUACAAUUCAAGUGUGAGAAUGCUGUGUUAACUAUUCUUUGGAAUUCUCCUUCUGUCCAGCAAAUACUCUAAUGAUGGUUAAACAUGGCACCUACUCAGCAAUGCCUUCCUGGACCACAACCCCUAUCCCCCUGCCCCACCCUCCUCAUUAAAAACAAAUACUUCUACUGUUUGGGUGUGUGAUAGGGUUCUCAAUGCAGAUCUCCCUUUUCUAGUUAGCUAUAUUCUUGACUGCAUCCGCUAAAAAUGUUAAAGCUUCUUGAGAGACAGACAUGCCAGAUUUUCUUGGUAUCUCCCAUAAUACGACCUACAGUCCAUGGUCUACAGAUGUUUUAAAUAGAAUUGCUAUUCUCGAUACAUACAAAGACGUAAUUGCUGACCCACAAUCAGUAACAUCCAUAUUGAGAGAUUUUUCAAAGGAUGGUGACCCUGCUUGUAUUUAUUUACCUUGGUAUUUUUUCUUGCAUCCUUCUGUGAUUCAAAAAAGUAAAAUGUGGCUUUCUGAAAUGAUGGAUAAGAGUCUACAUCUUCUAGAAAAAAUACAUAAAGGAGUAGUUAAGCUCUGUAAAUGUGCCACGAGCUCCAACACGACCAUCGUAGGGUGAAGCCCACGUUUUCUUCCAUGGCCUCAAAGGCCCUAGAACUUGCCUACCUUUCUGGCCUUACCUCCUAGCUACUUAUCCAUCUCUUGAACUUUAUACUCUUGUAUAAAUUUCUAACUUUCAGAAAAUGCCAUACUCUGUUUUGGCACCACACAUGUAUAUUUCCCCCUGGUACACUUGGAAGACUCUUAUCCAUCUGUGAAACCCUAUGUUGUCAUCACUUGGUCCAUGAAAUAUUACCUGGCCAAUAUCCCACCAUCACCUCAAACCCAAUCACCCCCUCCUCUGUAUGCUGUCACACCUAUAUUAUUAAACUUAUCACAUUGCAUUGUAAUUACUUCCUGACCUUUGUAUCUACUCUUUUAGUAACUGAUGUAUAUAUCUGAAAGGAGAGAUUGUUUCAUUGUGCAAUCAAUAAAUGUUUGAUAAAAUAAA